GGAGCUCUCUGGAUGGCGCGCUGUAUAGGGCUGUGGAUGUUCUGUGCUCUCAGGAAGGCGUGUUGAGUAGCCGGCACGGCGAGGCCCGUGCUGGCCGUUUCUUCCCGGAGUUUUCGUUUCUGUACCCCACUUUGUGUUUACUGCGGCAGGAGGCGCCAGCUAGCCCACAGGCUGUUCGGCCUAGGGGGUCGUACCUUCCUAACUUCACCACUCUCUGGGAAGACACCGCACCCACAGUAGGGUCGCUCGGGCCUCGCGGGCUGCACCUGUCUCUGCGGAGUUCCCCCGGCGCGGGCGGACGUCACACAGGGGCGUUCCAGCACUCCGGGAGCCCGAUUGCGAGUUUGUGAGAGUCCUUGGUGGAGGAGGUUGGAAAGCGUUCUCCCUCCCACAAAACCCGGUGCAGAGGGAGGGAGAGCCAGGUCCGUAGCGUGGGUCCAAGAAACUAUGGAUCCUGGAAGUGAGCACACUUUUGUGUCUUAAAAAGUUUGGUGUCUCGUUUUGAGGUGAAAAAUGAAUGAGAUAAGUGCUUUUUAAAAAGAAGUCUUCUAUUGUUCAACAGUUAUGAACAAGGACUAUCAAAAAUUUUGGUCAUCACCUUCAGAUCCUGUACAUUUUGAAGUGGAUACUUCUCAUGAAAAAGUAGAAAGCAUGUCAGAAUCGGAUACCAUGAAUGUCAGCAAUCUUUCUCAAGGUGUAAUGCUUUCACAUUCUCCAAUCUGUAUGGAAACCACCGGCACCACUUGUGACUUGCCUCAGAACGAAAUAAAGAAUUUUGAAAGGGAAAAUGAGUAUGAAUCCACACUUUGUGAAGAUGCUUAUGGCACACUAGACAAUUUGUUAAAUGAUAACAACAUUGAAAAUUACUCAACGAAUGCACUAAUUCAGCCAGUUGACACCAUCAGCAUAUCUUCCUUGAGACAAUUUGAAACCGUUUGCAAAUUUCACUGGGUAGAAGCAUUUGAUGAUGAAAUGACAGAGAAGCCAGAAUUUCAAAGUCAAGUGUAUAAUUAUGCAAAAGACAACAAUAUAAAGCAAGACUCAUUUAAGGAAGAAAAUCCAAUGGAAACUAGUGUUUCUGCAAAUACAGACCAACUUGGUAACGAGUAUUUUAGACAGCCUCCUCCUAGAAGCCCGCCUCUAAUCCACUGCAGUGGAGAGAUGCUGAAAUUUACAGAAAAGUCACUGGCUAAAAGUAUUGCCAAGGAAUCUGCCCUCAACCCUAGCCAACCUCCAAGCUUCUUAUGUAAGACUGCAGUUCCUUCAAAAGAAAUACAGAAUUAUGGGGAGAUUCCUGAGAUGUCAGUCAGUUAUGAAAAGGAAGUCACAGCAGAGGGUGUGGAGAGGCCAGAAAUUGUCUCAACUUGGUCUUCGGCAGGCAUUUCCUGGAGGAGUGAAGCAUGUCGGGAGAACUGUGAGAUGCCUGACUGGGAGCAAAGUGCUGAAAGCUUACAACCUGUUCAAGAGGACAUGGCUUUAAAUGAAGUCUUGCAGAAAUUAAAACAUACUAACAGAAAGCAGGAAGUGCGAAUCCAAGAACUCCAGUGUAGUAACCUGUAUUUAGAGAAGAGGGUUAAAGAACUACAGAUGAAGAUUACCAAACAGCAAGUGUUCAUUGAUGUCAUCAAUAAGCUAAAGGAGAAUGUUGAAGAAUUAAUUGAAGACAAAUACAAAAUAAUCCUAGAGAAGAAUGAUACUAAAAAGACAUUGCAGAAUUUGGAAGAGGUUUUAGCUAACACGCAAAAACAUCUUCAGGAAUCCAGGAAUGACAAGGAAAUGUUACAGCUUCAAUUUAAGAAGAUCAAGGCUAAUUAUGUGUGUUUACAGGAAAGGUACAUGACUGAAAUGCAACAAAAAAAUAAAUCUGUAAGUCAGUAUUUAGAGAUGGACAAAACCUUAAGCAAGAAAGAAGAAGAGGUAGAGAGACUACAACAACUCAAAAAAGAACUGGAAAAGGCCACAGCUUCUGCUUUGGACUUGUUGAAACGGGAAAAAGAGGCCCAAGAACAAGAGUUCUUGUCUUUACAGGAGGAAUUCCAGAAACUUGAAAAGGAAAACCUGGAAGAAAGACAGAAACUGAAAUCUAGACUUGAGAAAUUGCUCACUCAAGUUAGAAAUUUGCAAUUUAUGUCUGAAAAUGAAAGAACGAAGAAUAUAAAACUUCAGCAGCAAAUCAACGAAGUAAAAAAUGAGAAUGCAAAACUUAAACAGCAGGUUGCAAGGAGUGAAGAGCAAAAUUAUGUCCCUAAAUUUGAGACAGCUCAGUUAAAGGAUCAAUUAGAGGAAGUCUUGAAGUCAGAUAUUACCAAGGAUACAAAAACGACACAUUCUAAUCUGCUCCCGGAUUGCUCACCUUGUGAAGAGAGGCUGAAUCCUGCAGAUAUAAAAAGAGCUUCUCAGCUGGCCUCCAAAAUGCACAGUCUUCUGGCUCUGAUGGUGGGACUUCUCACAUGCCAGGACAUCAUCAAUUCUGAUGCUGAACAUUUCAAAGAGAGUGAGAAGGUUAGUGAUAUAAUGCUGCAAAAACUGAAGAGCCUCCAUCUUAAAAAGAAAACUUUAGAUAAAGAGCUACUGAAACAUAAAGAUAGAAUCACAACCUUUAGAGAGUUAAUUGCUAAGGAAAAAGCAUUUCAAGAUCAUGCUAUUAAGGUCAUAGACUGUGAUUCAGAUGAAGCCAAGAGUAUCAGAGAUGUACCUACCCUUCUGGGAGCCAAACUGGAUAAGUACCACAGUCUAAAUGAGGAGCUUGAUUUCUUGAUCACAAAACUGGGACAUCUCCUAGAGUCAAAAGAAAACCACUGCAACAGACUCAUUGAAGAAAAUGACAAGUAUCAAAGACAUUUAGGCAACUUAAUAAAGAAGGUUACAUCAUAUGAAGAAAUCAUUGAAUGUGCUGACCAAAGGCUUGCAAUAUCCCACUCCCAGAUUGCACAUUUGGAAGAGAGAAAUAAACAUUUAGAGGAUUUAAUUAGAAAGCCCAGAGAAAAAGCCAGAAAACCAAGAUCAAAAAGCUUAGAAAAUCAUCCGAAGUCCAUGACCAUGAUGCCAGCUCUUUUUAAAGAAAAUAGAAAUGAUUUAGAUUAAACAAGCCUGAAGAUUAAACAGUAAUCAUUUUUGUCAACCACUCCAGGAAGAGUCAUUACUACAUAUGCUAGCCAAAUCAAUCCAUGCAGAUGAUAUAUUAAAAUCUGUAUAAAGGGUAAAGUCUUACAUUCCAAAGAUGUGAUUACUUUUCUUCUAAUUUCUUCCUGUGAAUAAUCAAAUAUAUUCUAUUUAACAUAAA